CCUGCCUCACACUGGCCUCUCUCACGCUGAGGGAGGUCAGCGUGAGGCCCUGCCUCACACUGGCCUCUCUCACGCUGAGAGAAGUCCUCCCUCACGCUGGCCUGUUGAGGCCCAGUUCAUGCCUCUGUUGGCUUCUCCAGGCCCAGCCCCUGCCUGUUGGCGGCCUCUACCUCAACAGUGGGCCCUCCACGCCCACCUCUUGCCUCGCCGUGGCCUCCUCGGGCCAGGCUCCCACCUUGGGGCGGCCCCCGCAGGCCCAGCUCCUGCCUCACGGCCCUCCGGAGGCCAAGCUCAUGCGUCAGGGCGGCCUCUCCCGGCCUGGCGUUUGCUCCUUUGCAUGGGCUCCAAAUCCUGCACUUCCUCCAGUCGUUCUCUCCAGGCCCAGCUCUUCCUCCCAGCAGCCUCUGCAGGACCAGACUGUCGUCAAGUAGGCCUGUCCAGGGACAGCUCCUGCCUCCCGGCAGACUCUGCAGGCCCAAGUCGUCCUCAAGUCAGCCUCCCCAGGCCCAGCUCCGGCCUCUCGGCGGCCUCUCCAGGUGCAAAAGUUCCUCGAGUCCGUCUCUCCAGGUCCAGCUCCUCCUGUCUCCCAGUGGCCUCUUUCAGCCCAGCCCAGCUCAUGCCUCCCGGCGGCCUUCCCAGGCCCCGCUUCUGACUUUCCGCGGCCUCUGCAGGCCCCGAACUUGACCUCCAGUCGGCCUCUGCAGGCCUGGCCUCCUGCCUCCCGAAAGCUUGCACAGGCCCAGCCUCUGCCUCACAGCGGACCCUCCACGCCCAGCUCGCUCUCGCCUGCGGCCUCCCGAGUCCAAAGCUCCGGCCUC